GUUGCUGGGAAGAUGGCGACCGCGGCGACUAUCCCAUCGGUAGCCACGGCCACAGCAGCGGCUCUCGGCGAGGUGGAGGAUGAAGGGCUCCUGGCGUCGCUGUUCCGGGACCGCUUCCCCGAGGCCCAGUGGCGCGAGCGGCCCGAUGUGGGCCGCUACCUCCGGGAGUUGAGCGGCUCGGGGCUGGAGCGGCUGCGGCGCGAGCCCGAGCGCCUGGCGGAGGAGCGGGCGCAGCUGCUGCAGCAGACGCGCGACUUGGCCUUCGCUAACUACAAGACCUUCAUCCGCGGCGCCGAGUGCACCGAGCGCAUCCACCGCCUGUUUGGCGACGUGGAGGCGUCGCUCGGCCGCCUGCUCGACCGUUUGCCCAGCUUCCAGCAGAGCUGCAGGAACUUUGUGAAGGAAGCCGAGGAGAUCAGCUCCAACCGCCGGAUGAAUAGCCUGACCCUAAACCGGCACACAGAAAUUUUGGAAAUACUGGAGAUUCCUCAGCUCAUGGACACCUGUGUCCGGAACAGUUAUUAUGAAGAGGCCCUGGAGCUUGCAGCCUACGUACGCCGACUGGAGAGGAAAUACUCUUCCAUCCCUGUCAUCCAGGGCAUCGUGAACGAAGUGCGCCAGUCCAUGCAGCUGAUGCUGAGCCAGCUGAUCCAGCAACUGAGGACCAACAUCCAGCUUCCUGCCUGCCUCCGUGUCAUUGGCUACCUGCGGCGCAUGGACGUCUUCACUGAGGCUGAGUUGAGGGUGAAGUUUCUUCAGGCCCGAGAUGCUUGGCUCCGGUCCAUCCUGACUGCCAUUCCUAAUGAUGAUCCCUAUUUCCAUAUUACAAAAACCAUCGAGGCCUCCCGUGUCCAUCUCUUUGAUAUCAUCACCCAGUACCGUGCCAUCUUCUCAGACGAGGACCCACUGCUGCCCCCUGCCAUGGGUGAGCACACUGUGAAUGAGAGUGCCAUCUUCCAUGGCUGGGUGCUACAGAAGGUCUCACAAUUCCUGCAGGUGCUGGAGACCGACCUUUACCGGGGCAUAGGCGGCCACCUGGACUCUCUGCUGGGCCAGUGCAUGUACUUUGGGCUGUCCUUCAGCCGGGUGGGAGCUGAUUUCCGGGGUCAGUUGGCUCCUGUUUUCCAGCGGGUGGCCAUCAGCACUUUCCAGAAAGCAAUUCAGGAAACAGUGGAGAAAUUCCAGGAAGAAAUGAACUCCUACAUGCUCAUCUCGGCUCCAGCCAUCCUGGGCACCAGUAACAUGCCUGCUGCUGUGCCAGCCACCCAGCCGGGGACGCUGCAGCCACCCAUGGUGCUCCUAGAUUUCCCACCCCUCGCCUGCUUUCUCAACAAUAUUCUGGUUGCCUUCAAUGAUCUGCGCCUCUGCUGCCCUGUGGCCCUGGCGCAGGAUGUGACUGGGGCCUUGGAAGAUGCCCUUGCCAAGGUAACUAAAAUAAUCCUGGCCUUCCAUCGCGCUGAAGAGGCUGCCUUCAGCAGCGGGGAGCAAGAGCUCUUUGUCCAGUUCUGCACUGUCUUCCUGGAAGACCUUGUUCCGUAUUUAAAUCGCUGUCUCCAAGUCCUUUUUCCACCAGCUCAGAUAGCACAGACUUUAGGUUCAAGCGAUUCUCCUGCCUUAGCCUUCCCAAGUAGCUGGGAUUACAGGCCUGCGCCACCAAGCCCGGCUAAUGUUGUAUUUUUAAGAGAGAUGGGAUUUCUCCGUGUGGGUCAGGCUGGUCUCGAAUUCCUGACCUCAGGCAUUCCUCCCACUCAGCUCUCCAAGUACGGUAACCUAGGGCAUGUGAACAUCGGCGCCAUUCAGGAGCCCCUCGCCUUUAUCCUGCCAAAGAGAGAGACGCUUUUCACCCUGGAUGACCAGGCGCUGGGGCCCGAGCUCACAGCUCCAGCACCAGAGCCUCCCGCCGAGGAGCCACGCCUGGAGCCCGCGGGCCCAGCCUGCCCGGAGGGAGGGCGAGCGGAGACGCAGGCCGAACCGCCCAGCGUGGGGCCCUAGCCGGCGUCCCCUGCCUCCAGAACGCGGGCUGGACCCCAAUGGAGAACAGGUGGUGUGGCAGGCGAGCGGGUGGGCAGCCCGCAUCAUCCAGCACGAGAUGGACCACCUGCAGGGCUGCCUGUUUAUUGACAAAAUGGACAGCAGGACGUUCACAAACGUCUAUUGGAUGAAGGUGAAUGACUAAAGCUUUGCUACUGGGGCUGAGGAUUCCGGAUACCAAGACGCAAACACUUUCACUUUGAGCUGGGCAAAUCUUACUUGGCAUCAACUUGGAUGGCUCGCAUAUGACAGGAAACUGGAUUGCCAAGGCAUGGCAGACUGAGCUGGAGGAAGAUGUCAGAAAUGUUUGCCCUGAAAUCAGUUACGGACAAAAUGUUGGCUACAACUUGAGGAGAAAAAUCACCCCCAAAGGAGUGGACAUUUCCUAACAAUUCUGUAUGGAGGAAGGUGGGGUAAUUGCAUUCGUCUGCAGUAGACACGAGUUCCUCGGACCUGUAUAAUCUCCCAAAGCCAAGGUUUGGUAAUAAUGUAGUCCCCAAAUACCUGAAAGCUGUCUUUAAAAAUGCAGGUAAGCAUGUGACUGGCCAUUUGUGCCGAGUUCUUAUUUUUACGGAGGGCUUGUGGCCUUAGACGCCAGUUUGCUUAUGGAAAUGAAAGAGAAUAGUCCCUGUUCAAGGAUGUGUUUCAUGACAGCACGAGUGUAAAUGAGUGCCCACACAUUUUAACAGCCUUGGGCAGGAUUUUGCUGCUGAGAUCCCUAGAGCAGCUGGUUCUUGGCUCAUUCUUGGGGUAGAGGCCGUGGAUCAGGGCUGGGGGCAGGGGUGACAAUUGAGAAGUGCACUGAGCCCUUUCCUGUUAACAAUUGGGCAUAGAAAGCAGGAUUAGUACUUCCUGGUUAUACACUUAUUUUGUAAAAAUAGAAUUAAUAUCACAGCAACCAAUGUGUAGGUUUAAGAAAGUGGCCAGGUGCAGUGGUUCACGCCUGUAAUCCCAGCACUUUGGGAGGGCGGGGCGGGUGGAUCACGAGGUCAGGAGCUCAAGACCAGCCUGGCCAAGAUGGUGAAACCCUGUCUCUACUAAAGAUACAAAAAUUAGCCGGGCGUGGUGGCGAGCACCUGUAAUCCCAGCUACUCGUGAAGCCAAGGCAGAGAAUUACUUGAACCCAGGAGGCGGAGGUUACAGUGAGCUGAGAUCACGCCACUGCACUCCAUCCAGCCUGGGCGACAGAGCGAGACUCAAAAGUAUGAUUCUGGCUGUAGAGUUUUCUUUUUUUCUCUGUCUCAAAAAAAAAAAGUGUCAGCUUUGUCUUGUCAAGAGGUGAAGGAACUUGUUUUAUUCUUUUAUUUUUUUUUUAAGAUAGAGACGGGGGUCUUACUAUGUUGCCCAGGCUGGCCUCAAAUUCCUGGUCUCAGGCAAUCCUCCUGCCUCGGCCUCCCAAAGUGCUGGGAUCAGUUGUGAGCCACACUACCCAGCCAAACUCCAGUUUUAGUUAAACUGUUUCACCUCAUUUUUAUGCUGAGUUUUGUAAAGUAGGUAUUCUUGCUGAACAGAGUCCUGAAAAUCAAACUAUACAAGUAGUAGGAAGUCCAUUAAGCUGUUUAGAGGAAAAAGUGUUAUAAAUGGCAGUUAAAUGAACCCAGGAAAGACCCAUCCUCCUUUGUGGCUUUCUCUGAGGCCCCAUGAGGCCAAGCAGAAGCAAACUGGCUCUAGGUGCAGCCAGACUUUGAAAAGGAAUCCCGGCCAGGCUUGGUGGCUCAUGCCUGUAAUCCCAGCACUUUGGGAGGUCAAGGCAGGCAGAUCACCUGAGGUCAGGAGUUCAAGACCAGCCUGGCCAACAUGGCGAAACACUGUUUCUACUAAAAAUAUGAAAAUUAGCUGGGUGUGCUGGUAGGCGCCUGUAAUCACAGCUACUUGGGAGGCUGAGGCGGGAGAAUCGCUCAAACCUGGGAGGCAGAGGUUGCAGUGGGCUGAGAUCUCGCCACUGUACUCCAGCCUGGGCGACAGACCAAGGCUCUGUCUCAAAAAAAAAAAAAAAAAAAAAAAAAGGGAAUCCCAACCAGAUACUGGUGCAAGGUCAGAGAUGCAGCCAAUGGGGAGAUUUGUAGAAAGCUCAUAGAUGCUAAAAACAUGGGUCUUUAGGAAAAUUAGAAUUCAGCUGAGCCUCCUUUCAUUUGGACAAUGUUCAGAAGCUCUUACAGGGGGCUAUGGCAAUCUUUUGAUGCUUCUUAUAGCUUUCUGAGGUUAACGCUUUUGUGGUGGGCAUCGGUAGCAAUAAAAUGCAAACUUUAUUGCAUUUCCAGUAAAAUCUCUCCCACUUUGAGCAGGAAGCACUCACAAAAAACGCAUAUACAUGUCAACGUUGUGAGCUCAUCAGAGUUUUAGAAAUCAACUUCCACAGUGAAAGCCAAUGUAGGCAGAAGGUUUAUAACAGAAUCCCCAGGCAGAGAAGUGAAUUUCAGAGCAUUUCAGGGAGGAAACUCCUCUGCACAUGUCAGCAUGUUUAACAUCGAUGAUGGCAGGUUGUGUGCUGGCAGCCAGAGUCUGAGGCCACUGUCCAAAGUUCAGCGUCAGUGGUUCCUGUUGCUGGUCAUGGAGAGAGACAACUGGAAAGUCAGGUGUCUUCACGCUCUAACUAGAGCACAGGGAUGGACCAUAGCCAUGCUAACCUUUGUUAACCCCUAGGACUUGUCAAGGUGUUUAAGCAGUAGGAAUGAGGAAACAACGUUCUGAUUCAAGUAAAUGUAACUAGAAGUAAAAAUUUAAAAACUUGUAAGCUCA